GUUCCCGCAAGGUCGCUUUGCAGAGCGGGAGCGCGCUUAAGUAACUAGUCCGUAGUUCGAGGGUGCGCCGUGUCCUUUUGCGUUGGUACCAGCGGCGACAUGACGGGGUACACUCCGGAUGAGAAACUGCGGCUGCAGCAGCUGCGAGAGCUGAGAAGGCGAUGGCUGAAGGACCAGGAGCUGAGCCCUCGGGAGCCGGUGCUGCCCCCACAGAAGAUGGGGCCUAUGGAGAAAUUCUGGAAUAAAUUUUUGGAGAAUAAAUCCCCUUGGAGGAAAAUGGUCCAUGGGGUAUACAAAAAGAGUAUCUUUGUUUUCACUCAUGUACUUGUACCUGUCUGGAUUAUUCAUUAUUACAUGAAGUAUCAUGUUUCUGAAAAACCAUAUGGCAUAGUUGAAAAGAAGUCCAGAAUAUUCCCUGGUGAUACAAUUCUGGAGACUGGAGAAGUAAUUCCACCAAUGAAAGAAUUUCCUGAUCAACAUCAUUAAAGAUUAUGUAAAAAGUUAAAAGGCUUAUGAGCCUAAGUUUGUUCCUAUAUUACCAUAUUUACUGAAUUUUCUGGAAAAGUAACUUUAAUAAAGUUUAAUCUCAGAAAUUGUCAUAUCUGUUUUCAAGCAUUGUACAAUUUGAGACUGAGUAAUUUAACAAUAAGUAAAAAGUGGACAUGCUAAACAAAUAUGAGAGACUACCUACUUUUUCUGGUCAUUCUUGACUUGGAAAACGGUAUGGAAAAGUAUUUAGUUACAUGUUUGUUUGUUUUUUUCUUACACAGUACUUACACUAAUUUGGUAUCAGGGUAUGCAACAGUGAAAUAUCACAAUAAACAAAUGUAAGAACAGCAAUUCCAUGCACUUUUGUUUUAAGGAAAUCUUUCCGGCCAGGCGCAGUGGCUCAUGCCUGUAAUCCCAGCACUUUGGGAGGCCGAGGCGGGCAGAUCACGAAGUCAGGAGAUCGAGACCAUCAUGGCUAACACAGUGAAACCCCGUCCCUACUAAAAAUACAAAAAAAUUAGCCGGGCGUGGUGGCGGGCUCCUGUAGUCCCAGCUACUGCGGAGGCUGAGGCACGAGAUUGGUGUGAACCCAGAAGGCGGAGCUUGCAGUAAGCCGAGAUAGUGCCACUGAGCCUGGGCGACAGAGCAAGACUCCGUCUCAAAAAAAAAAAAAGCUUUCCGAAUCAUUUUUGAAGAAUUUAGAAACUUGAUUGAAAAGCUUAUUCCAACUAUGAUCUGACACUCAAGACUGUCAGAUUUAGGUUGCUGUUAAUUUUGUCAUGAGAAUGUAAAAUACUAAAAUCUCUAAGUGAAAAAUUUGCAUACUAGUGCUUGUUAUAAAGGAUAAUGCAAAAAUAAACUUGGGAACUUUG